CAUGUAGAGCCUUGAAAGCUAUUGUAAGGACAUUGGCUUUUAUGGGGAAUCUUUGGAGGGUUUGGGGAAGAAGAGUGACAUGAUCUCACCUGAAUUCUCAGUGAAUCACUCUGACUUCUCAAUGAUGAGAAUCUGGCUUCUCAAUGAUGAGAAUAGACUUUGUGGGUGGGCAAGUUAGGUCGUGGAAGUAGGGGGGCUAUUUAUAUAGCCAUUGCAAUAAUCCAGGUGAAAGAUGAUAGUGGCUUAGACCAAGUGAAAGCAGUGGAGAUGAUAAGUGGAUGGGGUAAAGAUAUGUCUGAUAGUUGAGCUGAUAAAAUUUUCUGACAGUUUAAAUGUGAUGUGAGUUGAGCUGAUAAAAUUUUCUGACAGUUUUAAUGUGAUGUGAGAGGGGAAAAAAAUAGAGGAAUUGAAGGACUUCAAGGUUAGUGGCUGAGCAAUGGGAAGGAAAGAUUUGCCAUUAACUGAGAUGGCAAAACUGCAGAUAGAACAGGUUUAGGGGGAAGAUGAAGAGUUCAGUUUUGAAUGUUGUUACAUUGAGAUGUUCAUUAGAUGUCCAAGGGAAGAUGUCAUCAAGAAGUAGCUGCAUACUUGGGUCUGGGAGGGGGUGCCAGCUGGAGGCAUAGUCAGGAAAUCAUGGAGAUGCUAAGCAUGAUAUUAUUCAUUACUUGGACUUAGGGAGGCUUCAUCAAGAGUCUGUCUAUUCCUUAUGAAACCCAGACUGUUAUUUUUUCAAGUCCUUUAUAAACAACAAAAUUCAAUCAAUCAACUGUAUUGUGAGCCUUUUGUGCCCACAGAUUUUGCCUUAUUUUUAAAAGCAUAGGGCUCGGCUUAUCAUGUGUUUGCUGAUGAAAACAUCGGUACUUCUAAAUCAGUGAAAAAUAUCUUGGAAAGAAGCUUAAAAGAAGCCUUUUCGCAACCAAGUAAAAUGUAAAUCAAUAUAACAAACACUCAGCGCCUGUUAUGGGCAUGUGGGUGCACACUGUGGGUGCUGAGGAACAACAAGAAAGGAACCCUCAAGGAAUUCACAGGCGAGUGGGAGGGAAAAGAAAAAUCCUCAAACACUUACGACACAAGCAAUAGAUAAUAGGACCCUAAGAGGGAUAUGAAUAAAGCCCAGUGGGCGAUCAGGAAGCGUUUCGAGAAGGAGGCAGCAUACCAGUCAAAUCUUGAAGGAUGGGAGAGGGGAAUGCCCUUGAAGAGCAGGUGGUUCAUUUUAGCUUGAGCACGAUACAGGUAGAUGCAAAGAUGUCCAAAGAUUCUUUAUUUUACCUUUGCUUUUGAAAAUUAUUUGGACUAUAGAAUUCUAGACAGAAAAUGUUUUUCUUUCAGCACUUAAAAAUGUUACUCUACUAUCUUCUCACUUGCAUUGUCUCCAUUGAAGAAGGCUGCUGUUAUCCUUAGCUGUGUUUCUCUCUGUGGAAUGUGCCAUUUUUCCUUUGGCUGCCUUUAAGAUUUUCUCUUCAUCAUAUGUUUUAAACAGUUGUAUGUCAUUUUCUUCAUGUUUCUUGUCUCUGGAGCUUCUUUAGCUUGUUGAAUCUAUGGGUUUAUAGUUUUAAUUGAAUUUUGGAAUUUUUUUUGCCAUUGGUACUUCAGAAAAGUUUCCGUCCUCCCUGCCAGCACUGGACUCUAAUUACACGGGUAUUGGGCUACUUGAAGUUGUCUCAUAGCUCACGAAUACUCUGCUCACUUUUAAAAAGCAUUUCUUCUCCAUGUGUUUCAUUUUGGAUAGUUUCUACUGCUAUAUCUUCAAGUUCACUAACCUUUCAUCUGCAAUGUCUAAUUUGCCCUUAGUCCUAUCCAAAAUAAGCCCUGUACUUAUUUUUUCUUUAGAGACAGGCUCUCGCUCUGUCACCCAGACUGGAGUGUAAUGGCACAAUCAUAGCUCACUGCAGCCUUGAACUCCUGGGCUCAAGUCAUCCUUCUGCUUUGGCCUCCCAAAGUGCUGGGAUUACAGGUGCGAGUCACUGCACCUGGCCUGGUUUACUUUUCAUAUCAGACAUUGUAGUUUUCAUUUUUAGAGUUUGAGUUGGGUGGUUUUUAUAUCAUUUAUAUUUCUGUUUAGCAUGUUCAAUCUUUCCUCUAGCUUCUUGAACAUACGAAAAUGGUUAAUAAAAAUAGCCAUUUUAUUGUCUUUGUCUACUAAUUUUUUUGUAUCAUUUCUGAGUGGGUUUCAAUUAAUUGAUUUUUCUCCCUCAUUAUUGGUUGUGUUUUCUUGCUUCUUCAAAGAUCUGGUAAUUAUUAUUGACUGUUAGACAUUGUGAAUUUUACCUUGUUGGGUGCUAUAGCUCAGUGAGGCACCCUUUAAUUACCAAGGGGAAGAAAUAGCCUUGAGUAAGUUCCACAUGGCUGACCAUACCAGAAACUACACAUUCUAACCUCAUGCCAAAAAUGUCCUACUGUUUAUUUAGCAGUCAAAUAAGAAUUCAAAGCACAAAAACAACAGAAGAUAAAUACAAGUGUGAAGCUGGUACUUCAACAAAUGGCUCUAAAAUUGGAGAAUCAGCAGCCUGGAAUUAAGCCAGACUAGCUGGGAAAAGUAUUAGAGUCUUGGUAGUUCAAAGGUGUUUUUUAAAGAGGAGAGCCCAACUCUUGAUGGAUUGGACCACUGACACCAAGAAGGGGCUGCAGGUGUUUGAUUAUGGUGACAGUAAUUUUUAAAAAAUAUGUUCAUUUGUUAUUUAAAUUUUUUUCAUUGUAUGAGAUUUUUUCAUUAAUUUUCUUUAUUUUUAAUUGGAGCUUUUAAUCUUUUCUUUACUAAUUUGCAAGUGCUCUUUAUAUAGGAAAGUUAUUAAUUUUUUGUGUAUAAUACACGUUUCCAUAUUUUUCCUGUAAUAACAAUUAUAAUGUUUAUUGAGAAUGUACAACAUGCCAGGUGUUAUGGUAACAGCAUUAGGUAUGUGUUUCAAAAAGGUCUUUAUCUUAUCCUGAUAAUAACUCUGUGAGGCAGUCAUUAUUAUUAUUAUCAUCAUUAUCAUUAUUCCCAUUUUACAGACAGGUCAUCGAGGUUUGGAGAGGUUGAACAUCCUGUGCAAGGUCACACAGCCAGUGAGUGGACGAGCUAGAAUUCAGAGUAUGUCUGACUCCCAAGUCCACGAUAUUUACACUACACCUUUGGCCUCAGGUGUUGUCUACAUUUUGUUUAUGGGCAUUUUGGGAACGGAUUGGACGUUUUUCAUUUUCAUGCAGUCAAAUCCGUAAAAUCUUUCAUUCUUGGGUUCUUCUUCUGCUUUUAUGUAUAGAAUGUUCUUUCCUACCUCAAGAUCUCAAGAUCAGGUAAAUAUUCACCUGCAUUUUCUCAUAAAUACGUACAAUUUCAGUUGAAAGCUAUCCUGUUACAUUUGUAUGUGUUUAAAACAGAGAUAAAAAGAGCCUGUCCCCUUUAAGAAACAAUUGUCCAGAAUAAGUUGCAGGACUCACAAAUAGGCAAUUCGCUACCAAACAACUUCUUAAAAAUAAAGUAAGGGCAAGGAUGUGAGAUUAGUAAAUGGAUUUACAGAUGCUUCUUUUUUUAUGACUGGGGAAGAACUGUCUCAGGGUCAGCUGCAGUAGUUAAGGAGAUAGAACGUCAAGUUGUCACUGUGUGUGUGUCUGUUUCUGACCGGGGAGAAGAACAAUCCAAACACAGCCAUAUUGGGAGAACACGGUCGGAGGCCACCUUUGGGAGUGGCUCAGGAUUUCUGGUUCUGGAACUGGGUCAGCCAGUUCAUGCAAGAAGGAGGCCUUGCUGCUGGCAGCUACCAUCUAACCAGGCAACUGAGGGAAAAGCACAAGGACUUGUCAUUACUGAGUGGCGGUUGCUUGAACUGAAGACUGGGCAAGGCUGAAAACCUGGGGCUUGAUAGAGCCUGUAGGGCUCCAGGUGGGAAAAGGGAAAGGUUUAGGAAGGUGGUUAUAAUGACCAAUGACAACUUACAAUUAGUGCAUUAAGGCACUUAUCCGUUUACACCUGGUUGUUUCUAUAAGUCUUAGUAAGAUUUAUUCAGAUUACAUUUUGAAUUCAGUUGUCAAACUGAGCUGGUGAUUAGACUUUCAUGAAUAUCUUUAUUAAAAUAGCAUGAAUUCAAAUAAGCGAGGUGGCUCACACCUGUAAUCCCAGGACUGUGGGAGGCUGACGCAGGAUUAUUUGAGCCCAGGUGUUUGAGAUCAGUCUGGGCAUCAUAGGCAGACCCCCAUCUCUACAUUAAAUUUAAAAACUAGCCAGGCAUGGUGGCACGUGACUGUGGUCCCAGCCACUCAGGAGAAUUGCUUUAGCCUGGGAGGUCGGGGCUGCCACUGCACUCCAGCCUGGACAACAGAGUAAGACCCUGUCUGAAAAAAAAAAAGUAUGAAUUGAGGAUUUUUCAGAAAGCAGAAUUAAUUGAUUGACAUUUAAAUCAUGACCAAAUGUGUUUCGAUAACAGUACAAACAUGCAAAGAGUGUUUUUAUAAGGACUUCUUAAUUUAAUCCUCAUAGCCACUCCUUGGGUAAAUACUGUCACCUUUCCUAUUGCAUUUCCUAUUUCAUCAGAGAGGCUGGGAACCUGUCCAGGAUCUUGCUGUGGUUAGUAAGAAGAACCUCCUAGGCCAUCUGCGGCCUCUGCUGGCUUAUCCAGCCUUCCCCUUGACCUGGGGUUGGAUCCUGAAGAAGAACACCUGGUGGGGGAAAUCCUCCUUCGGGGACUUCAGGCAUGCAUUUUCAGAUGUUCCCAAUGCUAAUCAUUGUCACAUGGAGUUUUUCUCCAAAGCCCUGAUUUCAACUGAAAGUCAUUUUGCCAGAGACAUUGGCGUGCAGGCGUUUGCUGGAACUGCCCCUUCCAAAUGAGAUUGCUGAGGAAUCCUGAGCAGAGCCCCAGCUCCUGUGACUGCCGUAGCCCUUGCGUGCAAGAGGGCUGGCCAGGGCUUGUGGGUGGACUUCAAACCAACACUUGGUAAUUAUUUGUUUAAGAUUUUAUUAGAGAAUCAGGGCAAUGAUGGAGGCGGAGCGGGAAGGAGCACUGCUAGAGGUUCCACCCAGUCUCCACCAAUUCAGUGCAGCUUUGCAGACUCGAUUCAGCAAAACAAAUGACUCGAGAAUAAGCCCUACCCCUUGAAAGGCAGGCUGGCGUCCAUCCCCAUCCUAAUCCACUUAGCAAAGCAGGAAGAUCUAGUGAAUACUAUGGUUUCCCCAUUGCAUUGCAUUUUCAGUGAUGUCUUAGCCUCCUUUACAUAUCAGCACCCCAGUGUCAGCCUGGCUGACCCAGCCCAGAGCAGCCCUGGGUGCAGCCACGCAAGUGCCCUGACUCAAGAUAGUGUGAAAGGCUUGUGUAUUAUUGCCCUACAGACCAGGCCACAUCAAUGGUCUCUGGUUUUGCUGUGAUGUUGAUAGAGACAGGAAGGGGAUAGCCAUGUCUCAGGAACCCUAACUAGAUAAUCCUAGCAUCUCCAAGGUCCUGUUUUCUAGGGAUUAUUGGAGUAGCUGCAAAAAUAAAAUUAUCCUAAACAAGCAGGCACAAAGAGAAGCAGGUAUCCCCAUGAGAGAUUUUCAGUUUCUGUAAACAAAGUGACUGCCUGUCUGAAAGGAAUAAUAUCAUUGCUUGGGGAGCACAUUCCCUUCCCAUUUGAGCAAGUAAUCAAUGCUGAAGUCUUUUUUGAGUACCUACUAUGUGCUUGAUGCCAUUCUGGUGCUGAGAAAGGGAAUGGAUAAGUGAAUGUGGCAAACAGAAAAAGGACAAAAUAGCCUCUACUAUUCAGAGUCUAGUUGAGAAGUCAGCGUAACAGCGAAAAAGUGAGCCAGUGACUGGCCACGCUGCUGGGCACAGAAACGGGCAGUCAGUAGGGACUGGGCUUUUUGGAAGGCUGAGAAAGAUUCUGCUGGACUCUGCAGAUCCCUGGCAGGAUGAACUGAUAGAACACUUGCCCCCCAGGCCGCUGAUGUGGGAUGGCAGAAGAUGGCUGGACAGGCUCACUUGAGCUGUUAAAUGCCUGCGGCCCAACACGAGCUGGGGCCUAGGAGUCACACCCCAGAAUUUCACUGUCGUGUUUCCAAGCAGCUGCAUACAAGAUAUAAAAAUUAGGUCAAGUUAGGAUUUUAAGAGUUUAUUGUGCAUACAAAGAAAUGUUCAUGAACUAAGAGACCUCAAACUGGAAAGUGGCAGAAAGUCUCAAAUUUACAGCAGUUACAGCUCAGUUUCAAGAGCAUAAAGGAGGAAGCGUUUUGGCCUGUUUCAGGAUUGGAUGUCAUAUAUUCUUUCUUAAGGCAUAUGACUAUGUAAGCUGAUUUGCCUAUAUCCGUUGGUUUAAUUUCAUUGAAUCAUGCUGAUAAGAUGAAAAGCUUACUGAGUGUUCUGUUUAUGUUGAAGGUUUAUGUUUUGGGGGGCAGGGAAUCAGUAAGAGCUAAGUUUUGGUUAUGUGGCUAUGAGUAAUUGGCCUUGGGUACUAAACUGUGGCCUCCAGUUUUAUUUAUUUACAUUUAACAAAGGCAAGACCCACAUUCCCGUUGGUGUUUGCAGAGUGCCCUCACCAAGUCUUGGCCCCUGUGUGAAUUCCUGCCUUUCCCAGAAAUGAGUCCAGGGUGUCUGACCUCAGCUUCAGAUCCCAUGAAGGAUUCUUCUAACAUCUGCGAUCUAACCCUCCAGUGACAAGCAGGUGGACCACCACAUUCAUAGCCCCAUCUCCCCAGUCCAAGCAAUCUCAGCCAAUGAUCCGAGUGAUGGUGGACCUGUGCAACAGCACCAAGGGCAUCUGCCUCACAGGACCUUCUGGACCACCAGGACCUCCGGGAGCCGGCGGGUUGCCAGGACACAACGGAUUGGAUGGACAGCCUGGUCCUCAGGGCCCAAAAGGAGAAAAAGGAGCAAAUGGAAAAAGAGGAAAAAUGGGGAUACCUGGAGCUGCAGGAAAUCCAGGGGAAAGGGGAGAAAAGGGAGACCAUGGUGAACUGGGCCUGCAGGGAAAUGAGGGCCCACCAGGGCAGAAGGGAGAAAAGGGUGACAAAGGAGAUGUGUCCAACGACGUGCUCCUGGCAGGUGCCAAAGGUGACCAAGGCCCACCCGGUCCACCUGGGCCCCCAGGCCCUCCAGGUCCUCCAGGGCCCCCUGGAAGCAGAAGAGCCAAAGGCCCUCGGCAGCCAAGCAUGUUCAACGGCCAGUGCCCAGGUGAGACUUGUGCCAUACCAAAUGAUGAUACCUUGGUUGGAAAAGCUGAUGAGAAAGCCAGUGAACACCAUUCCCCACAAGCAGAAUCCAUGAUCACUUCCAUUGGAAACCCAGUGCAAGUACUGAAAGUGACAGAGACAUUUGGGACUUGGAUAAGAGAGUCUGCUAACAAGAGUGAUGACCGGAUUUGGGUGACAGAGCAUUUUUCAGGCAUCAUGGUUAAGGAAUUCAAGGAUCAGCCCUCACUUCUGAAUGGCAGUUACACGUUCAUCCACCUUCCAUACUAUUUCCAUGGCUGUGGGCACGUUGUUUACAACAACUCUCUCUACUACCACAAAGGGGGUUCUAAUACCCUAGUGAGAUUUGAAUUUGGCCAGGAAACAUCCCAAACUCUGAAGCUUGAAAAUGCCUUGUAUUUUGAUCGAAAAUACCUUUUUGCAAAUUCCAAAACUUACUUCAAUCUAGCUGUAGAUGAAAAGGGCCUUUGGAUUAUCUAUGCGUCAAGUGUGGACGGCUCGAGCAUUCUUGUAGCACAACUGGAUGAGAGGACAUUCUCAGUGGUGCAACACGUCAAUACCACGUACCCUAAAUCCAAGGCUGGCAACGCCUUCAUUGCCCGAGGAAUCCUCUAUGUCACAGACACCAAAGAUAUGAGGGUCACAUUUGCCUUUGAUUUGUUAGGAGGGAAACAGAUCAAUGCAAACUUUGAUUUAAGAACUUCCCAGUCUGUUCUUGCCAUGUUAGCAUACAACAUGAGAGAUCAGCAUUUAUAUUCAUGGGAAGAUGGCCAUUUAAUGCUUUAUCCUGUGCAGUUUUUGUCAACUACCUUAAAUCAGUGAUGUGCUGCAUUCGGCUCCCUUCAGCAAAUUUCAGGGGUUUUCUGGGACCAGUUCUCCCCCAACAGGAAACUUGUUUUUUUAACGUCAGCCAGAUAUUUAGAAAAUAACCUCAAAAGUGUUUAUAUGGUCAGUGAGCCCCGCUUAGUGAAAUAGCAACAGAUUGGAAGUUGAAAUGGCUGAGAUUUGGUGAUCUCCCCACAGCUGGCUCUGCAAGUUACCUCUUUCUCCUUGGGCCUUAGUUUCCCCAUUGGUAAUCUGAAUUGGCUAAGAUGAUUGGGGAGAUUUUCUGUACCUGUAGGUAAUUUGGUGAUUCUUGGUGGCUGCUCUUCUCACAACUUUUAUGUAUCUGCUUCUGUCGUUUAGCUUUUUUAGCCACAUGCUGACCAAAUUUACCUUUGAGUUGAUAAGUCCAGUGGCUUGAGUAGUGAAUCCCUCAGUGCUGACUUAUAUCUUGUUCUUUGAAAAAAUGCAUUGACUCUUUAAGACAUCUAAAGUAUCACAUUAUCCAUAAUUUAUUGCUUUUCUUUGCAUCUGCACCUGCCACCACAGAAUAACCAUUACCCUCAGCUGCUGAUUGGGCAGCUCUGAGAUUAGCAAAAGCCAGGGACAGCUACAUGUUCAGGUUUUUUUUUUUUUUUUUUUUUCAAUAAGCUAUUUUUUUUCUUUUCUUAUUUUAAAUAGAGAGAGAGUCUUGCUAUGUUUCCCAGGCUGGUCUUGAACUCCUGGGGCUCAAGUGAUCCUCCUGCCUUGGCCUCCCAAAAUGCUGGAUUACAGGCAUGUGUGCCUGGCCCAGGUUUCUUAAUAAAACAGAAUCAUGAUCUUCCAGGUUCCCCCCAGUUUCUGAUCAUGUUGAUUUGUAGCUGUGGAUCAUGAACACUGAAUCCUCAGAUCACUCUGACUUCUUAUGCUUCUCCUGUGGAUCCACUAUCAAAGUACUAAAUGCUGUGUAAGUAGACGUUAAUCUGGCUGGAACCAUGGGAAGCACUUUGCAGUGUUCAGAAGAGAGGCUCCAUUUGUGGCUAUUAUGUAGAACUGGGCCAGAGCCAGUCCAUUGCCUGUUUUUUUAAAUAAGGUUUUACUGAGCACAGCCACACUCAUUUGUUUAUGCAGUACGGCCUGACAUUGCUUUUGCUCUGCAACAGCAGAGUCGAGUCAUUGCAACAAAGAGCAUAUGGCCCCACAGUGCCUAAAAUAUUGACCAGCUACCCCUUUAUGGAAAAAGAUUGCUGACUCCUGAUAAAGAAUAUAAAGUGAGCCUGAUUCUUGAAAAAAUCAGAACCAGAGCCUGUUUUGUUUUGUUCUAAACUAAGAAGCCGCAUAGGAUGUGACUUGCGUUUUGAGUAGAGGGGAAGGCUGAUAACGGCGUAAGAUGAAGUGGCCCUCCACAAAGGCUGGUUAGGGGACAGUUCUUUCUCUAACAUAGUUUUAAAGGAUGUGAUCUGGUCCCCUUGGAUGCCAGGAGAGAAUCCAGUUGAACUUGCUCCUAAAUGCUCUUAAAUAUGCAUAUUUUCUGCCAACUCACUUCUUUAAACAUCUUUCAGCCCAGCGCUGCGGCCCCGGGAAGGGCCACUGCGAAUAGAGAGGAAGCUGGAAAAGUUCCUGGGGCUCUGCAGCCAGGAAGGGGAACCAGGGCAAAUCUUAUGUAAAGAUUUUUCAGCAACUUGUCCCAAUUUGUGUGUAUUCUGAAACUUUCUCUUUGGGACCAAAUUCAUUCUCAAUGGCCCUGAGUUCAAUAUAUUAUUAACAGCAGUAUUUUAAAACUUAGGGUUGAACUGGGCAUGGUGGCACAUAACUGCAAUCCCAGCUACUUUGGAGGCAGGGAUGGGAGGAUCACUUGAGGCCAGGAUCUCAGGACCAGCCUAGAGAGAUCCCAUCUCUAAAAAAUAAAAUAUAAGAAAAUAAAACUUAGGGGAUAUACAGAUUUAAAUAUUCAAAUCUCCCUGCUCCCCUGAAAGUCCCCAGGCAGCUGUCAAUGACUUGUUUGUUGUGUUCUCAAUAUGAUGGCUAUUUGAAACUUCACCUACUUUUCAUUAGAUUGGUUGUACCAUGUCACCUUAGCUUUUAAAAAUACUCUUUUCAGAUUCACGUUCUCUAACAAAGAGUCUCAUGUUCAAGAUCAAUAUGUCUAAUAAGUGCUGGUGUCCUUUUAAAGUAUUUAAAUAUAUAUGUUGCUGUUGCUGAAUACAGGAGACCAGGUUAGGAAUAUAGUUUCAUAAUAAUAGUACAUACAAUACUAAUUGUAUAUAAGGUAGCAACCAAAAGAGGUUGUUAAUUAGCACAUAUUCCUUUUAGAAAAAUGUUUCAGAAACCUCAGUCUUGAUAUCUGAGCUAUCUGGGCUCCCUUACUUGUGAGUAAGGGAUCAUGCUCACCACUGGAGAAGCUUACACCGGGACUUUUUUUCUUUUUUCUUUUUUUUUUGCUAUGACAGAGUAAUGCUAACGUAAGGACAACUGAGUUUGAUCAGUGUUUAAUCGCAGUGGGUAAUCUUAUCUGAUUGUCUUUAAAAGUGAAAAGGAUUAAGAUUUUAUUCUUUCUUGUAAACAUUACUUGAUUUUUUAAAGAAGUUUUGGGCUCACUGCUAAAAUAGAGUAUACAACUGAAUGUUUUUAAGUCAAGAUACUGUUUUAGGAGUUUACCCUCUCAUUUAUAACCAAAGUUGCUCUAAAACACUUUCCAAAUAUCUGCACUUCUGAUGUCAGAAUCAAACCAGAUAAUUCUCUAAUUCUUCUUUAAUCUAAAGUAGAUAGCUUCCCACUGGAAAGUAAACAAAACCAUCCCUCCCAACCUCAAAGCUAGGCCACACUCUAUUUCAAGGCAUUUUCUUUCAGCUGAUAAGGUGUCCUCCUGAAGCCAAGUAGGUGGUUCUGGUCUCCAAGUAUCGUUAAGCACAGGUGCUAUGACAGAAAAAGUUCUGGGGUGGAAGUUUUAAGAUGAGGAGUUCUGAUCUUAGGCAUCUUAACAGUCACAAGGUGAAAAGUCAAAUGAAACAGUACAAUUCUUGAUGAGUGAGGUGUCAUCUUCCAACCACACAGAGGACGUUUUGGCUAUGAUCAUCUGAUGGCAAGUGAAGGAGAAAUGAGUGAUAGGGCUUUGCGUUUUCAUCCAGAUGCUGUGGCCCUGUGUUUCACAGCAUUAAGAGCCAUAAUUUCCAACCUGCACAGAUCCUGAACAACAAAUGAAUAACGAUGAAUGUCUUUUUGGUUGUAAUUUAACAAGUCAAAUAAAAUAAUCAUUGCUGAGCACAA